GCUUUCUCCUGAGCCGUCGGAGGGAGCCGGAGCGCUUCUCCCGAGUUGGUGAUAGAUUGGUGGUCAUCCAACAUGCAGAAAUGAAUGAGCAGUGAAAAGCAGCAGAGCCGAUGGGUCAUGAGGAUGUAAGUGCGUUUGAAGGCUUCCACACCCUCUACUCCAGGACAGAAUCAUGAAUAAACUGGAGGAUAAGCAGGACCAGAUGAUACCAUGAAGAGAAGUUUACAGGCCCUCUAUUGCCAACUGUUAAGUUUCCUGCUGAUCUUGGCACUGACCGAAGCGCUGGCAUUUGCCAUCCAGGAACCAUCUCCCAGGGAAUCUCUUCAGGUCCUCCCUUCAGGCACUCCCCCGGGAACCAUGGUGACAGCACCCCACAGCUCUACCAGACAUACUUCUGUGGUGAUGCUGACCCCCAAUCCCGAUGGACCCCCCUCACAGGCUGCAGCUCCCAUGGCAACACCGACACCCCGUGCAGAGGGGCACCCUCCUACGCACACCAUCUCCACCAUCGCUGCGACAGUAACCGCCCCCCAUUCUGAAAGCUCCCUGUCCACAGGGCCCGCUCCAGCAGCCAUGGCAACCACAUCCUCCAAGCCAGAGGGCCGCCCUCGAGGGCAGGCUGCCCCCACCAUCCUGCUGACAAAGCCACCGGGGGCCACCAGCCGCCCCACCACAGCGCCCCCCCGCACUACCACACGCAGGCCCCCCAGGCCCCCAGGCUCUUCCCGAAAAGGGGCUGGUAAUUCAUCACGCCCUGUCCCGCCUGCACCUGGUGGCCACUCCAGGAGUAAAGAAGGACAGCGAGGACGAAAUCCAAGCUCCACACCUCUGGGGCAGAAGCGGCCCCUGGGGAAAAUCUUUCAGAUCUACAAGGGCAACUUCACAGGGUCUGUGGAACCGGAGCCCUCUACCCUCACCCCCAGGACCCCACUCUGGGGCUACUCCUCUUCACCACAGCCCCAGACAGUGGCUGCGACCACAGUGCCCAGCAAUACCUCAUGGGCACCCACCACCACCUCCCUGGGGCCUGCAAAGGACAAGCCAGGCCUUCGCAGAGCAGCCCAGGGGGGUGGUUCUACCUUCACCAGCCAAGGAGGGACACCAGAUGCCACAGCAGCCUCAGGUGCCCCUGUCAGUCCACAAGCUGCCCCAGUGCCUUCUCAGCGCCCCCACCACGGUGACCCACAGGAUGGCCCCAGCCAUAGUGACUCUUGGCUUACUGUUACCCCUGGCACCAGCAGACCUCUGUCUACCAGCUCUGGGGUCUUCACGGCUGCCACGGGGCCCACCCCAGCUGCCUUCGAUACCAGUGUCUCAGCCCCUUCCCAGGGGAUUCCUCAGGGAGCAUCCACAACCCCACAAGCUCCAACCCAUCCCUCCAGGGUCUCAGAAAGCACUAUUUCUGGAGCCAAGGAGGAGACUGUGGCCACCCUCACCAUGACCGACCGGGUGCCCAGUCCUCUCUCCACAGUGGUAUCCACAGCCACAGGCAAUUUCCUCAACCGCCUGGUCCCCGCCGGGACCUGGAAGCCUGGGACAGCAGGGAACAUCUCCCAUGUGGCCGAGGGGGACAAACCGCAGCACAGAGCCACCAUCUGCCUGAGCAAGAUGGAUAUCGCCUGGGUGAUCCUGGCCAUCAGCGUGCCCAUCUCCUCCUGCUCUGUCCUGCUGACGGUGUGCUGCAUGAAGAGGAAGAAGAAGACCGCCAACCCGGAGAACAACCUGAGCUACUGGAACAACACCAUCACCAUGGACUACUUCAACAGGCAUGCUGUGGAGCUGCCCAGGGAGAUCCAGUCCCUUGAAACCUCUGAGGACCAGCUCUCAGAGCCCCGCUCCCCAGCCAAUGGCGACUAUAGAGACACUGGGAUGGUCCUUGUUAACCCCUUCUGUCAAGAAACACUGUUUGUGGGAAACGAUCAAGUAUCUGAGAUCUAACUACAGCAGGCAUCACUUUGCCAUUCCGUAUUUUUCGUCUCUAAAUUAUAAAUAUACAAAUACAUAUAUUAUAAAUAUAACCUUUGUGUAACCCUGACUUAAUGAGAAACAUUUUCAGCUUUUUUUCCUAUGAAUUGUCAACAUCUUUUUUACAAGUGUGGUUUAAAAAAAAAAAAAACUUUACAGAAUGAUCUGUGGCUUUAUAAAAUAAAGGUAUUUCUAAGCAAAGCAGUUGCAUUGAUUGCUUCUCUUAAUAACUAUUCUUGAGCACCUGGGGAUCCCAGGAACCCUGGUCAGGUGAGGUAAGAGACUGACCUCCUGUAGAAGCUGAAUGUUACAGUGCAAGCGCACGAUUCUUUGAGUGAUUCUUAAAGCUCUGGUUCCUCUUGAUUUGGUGUGACCCCAUUUCCUCCCUUCUCAUACGCACACCUGUAAAGGGAACUGGACCGCCUCAGGGGAAGACGGCAGACUCAUGCACAGAGAAGGAAAAGGGAACAUCUCAUCACCUCUGAGGAUGAGUACCCUGGAGCCUUAUGACGGCACCAUUGGAUGUCAUGUUUAAUUCCAUCCAAGUUGUGGAUGGCAGGCAGGAGCAUGGAGCCCUCAGGAAUCCAUGGAGGACAUCAAGGCAUCCCAAGGCCAUAUUCCCCUAACAUUACUUCCACUGCUAACAACAGGACUGCCUUUCCCUGGUGGGAAAAUGCUCCCUUUAUGCCCAUUCCUGUAUCCCCUCCAACACCCACAUCUGCAUUAAACACCCGUGCCUUUCUCUUGGAGAGGGUUUAGAUGCAGAUCCCGGCCCUGGAGCUUUAAAAUGCUUGCCCUUCCUUCUUCAAGGAUCAAAUGUUUAUUGGGGUUCAGCUUUGUUUUCUCAAAAGGCCAUGGUAUCGUGCCCCUGAGGAACAUGUUUAUCUAAGAAGCUUUGAGGUAGUAGAGCGAUAAUUUUUGAAACCUUCCUCCUGCAAUCUUUAAAAAAGAAAAAAAAGAUUGCCCAAACAAAUCAUUUGGGAGAAGACAUCAUUAUACUCCUACUUGGCACUGCAAACCUGCUCGCAGCACCAGCCGGUGGACUUGCCAUCCAGCUCUCAGCUUCCACUGCUCCCCUUGUUCCCGGCCGGCUGGCUGCCUCCCCGUGCUGUGUCCAGCACGGCCAACAACGUCAGACCCUCAGAGACGCCCAAGGGGCUUCCAGAGGUGGCCGCUUCUCUAUUUUUUCCUGAUUGUGGCUGAGAGAGAUGAUUACUGCUUUGACACUUCCUUUCUCUAAAAGAAAAAUAGUUUGAUAGUAUAUUUUGAAUAUAGAUGCUCUUAUAGUCAGAUUGGGAAUUGAACUUGAAUAUUGGGUCAUAUGUUUGUGUUGUUGCUGUAGUCUAUCAUGACUUUUUUCUUUCUGCAUUUUCCUUAAAAAAAAAAAAAAGAUGGCCUUCAAAAGUGUGUUCUCAAUGUUGUAUGAACCUCCUUCACAUGAGUUCGGUUGUUGUCUCUCUUCAAAGACUCUUCAACCCACAAAGAAGCAACUAAAUGUUUCUCUAAGUUUAAUUUUCUAGCGUGUUGUUGUCUUACCUUUUUAACCUUACCAUAAUAUUUCUGUUAACUGUUACAUUUAAUAUACCAAUGUGUGUAAGUAUACAGAGAAAAAUCUGUUUGUAAAGUAAAAUUUAUAUAUAAUAUAUGUAAUCAAAGAUACAUAUGUUAUAUAUACAUAUGUGGAUGUAUGACUUAUUUUUCCUUAUCCACAGAUUUCAGCUACCAUGUAUAUAUAAAUAAACUUAUUUUAUUAGCCAGAGGA